GGUUUUGUGAUGGCCGCGCCGUGGCUGCCUCCCUAGAGUCCCUCAGGGCCCUUUAAAUACCGCGUUGGGGGGGACACUGGGGCUGGGGGGGUUUGUUGGGCUGGUGAGUUUUCGAGGUGACUGUGCUGUGCUCGGUGAGGGGACGCCCAGAGAGCCCUGACCCGGGGUCACUCCGUCGCCGUUCUCCUCUUGUCUACGUGCUGGACCCGGUGCGUAUCCAUCACGGGGGAGGCGUUGCCGGCUCGGAGGUGACCGGCCAGGUCCAACGGAGGGGACACCGCUGCAGCCCGAAGGCUCCCCUGCCCUAUCUCGGAACUCCAUCCUGGGAAGGCGGGGUCAGGGGCCAUCAAGCUCGGCUCCUAGUUCAUGUCUUCCCACUCCGCGUCCCCUUGUUUGACCUCGAACUGCCGUCCCGCGUGGGAGCGGGGAGCGGGGCACCGAGUGGCCGCCCCGCGUGUCGGGGUGGACACGGACUUCGGGCCUCGGAGGCCGCUUCGCCGCUGUUUAAAUCCUGCUGGACAGGUACCAGCGGCAUCCCGCCAUCAGGGGCCCAGGGCACCCCCUUCCCCCACACUCCUCGGCCGGGCUGGAGUAGGGAACUGAGCCAGGGUAGAGGCAGGGCGGGCCCGGCAGCGUGUGUUUGGGAUUUGUUGCCGUGGUUUCCCCGGCACUCAGCUCUGCCUCCGCCGUCCCCUCCCCCAAGGGUUUGUUUUGACAGGAAACCUGGUGCUGCUGGAGGGGAGGGGCGGCCAGAGGACGUGGGUGAGGUCGUGCAGACUGCUGCUGCGUCCCCUUGCCGGGACCUUUGGUUAAGGGGAAGAGGUGGAGAAAAGCCGAUUGGGCCUGGGCUCGAACGCUGAACCCUCAGGUGUUGCUUGUGCUUCCCAAAGCUGCUACUGUAGGUGGCACCACUGGGGGUAAUAGCAAUGAUUUGAGGUGGCAUAUGGAUGAACAUAGUUACUUGUUUUCGUUACUAUUAAGAAAAUCUGUUCCAUUAAGUAAGCAGUUUCACAAUGAUAGAGUUUCCUUUUAAAAUAAAUAUAUUUAAAUGCAAAAAUCUAGUCAAGAUAGAGACGCGGUUACUAAAUUAUAGUAAAGGUAAGGAGGGAGACGUAGAAAUAGUCAUGAAGAGUGGCACUCAAACGACUUAAGUUUGGGAAAUCUUAGAUGGUUGUCCUGCUACCUUAACUGUGAAGAAACUGGACAAGUUGUCCUUGUCCCCAGUGGGUGUCUCAGCACCCAUGGUCACCAGCCCAGUCAGGGACUUUGCUCUUCUUACCUGCCAACGGAUAAUGAGUUAAUCUCAGUGGUUCCCACUUGAGGAGGCUCCCUGCCGUGGUCCUUUUCCUCUCUUCUCUAGGGAUUUCAUGCAUCACCCUGACAGCCAGUGGAAGUUGCCUGAUUUGAAGAGGCCCAGGGCCGAAGAUACCCAGUCAUGUGUGGAAGCAGCUUCAAUGCCAUUUUGUGAGAGGUUGAGGGCCCCAGAGGGGGAAGCACAGUGACCUGCUAUCGUGUUGGAGGCUUUGCUUGGAGUCAUCUUCAGUCUUUUCUGUUGACUUUACCUUUGACCAGUGAUUAAAUCCUCCAGGAGAUUCAGAAGUAGCCAUGGGAAGAAAGGAACAAGGAACUAAUGUACAAGGAACUAAGCGCUGUCAUGGAGAUACAGGAGACGCGCUGCAGACAUACCAAGAGGAGUGCUAUUCACUUUGGCUAGAAGCAAGGCUUCCUGGAGAAGGUGCUACCUUUUUACCCACACUUAAGUGACGCAAAAUGCCCUUCAAUGGCGAGAAGCAGUGUGUGGGAGAGGACCAGCCAAGCGAUUCUGAUUCUUCCCGGUUUUCCGAAAGCAUGGCUUCGCUCAGUGACUAUGAAUGCUCCAGGCAGAGCUUUGCAAGUGACUCCUCCAGCAAAUCCAGCUCUCCUGCUUCAACAAGCCCUCCAAGGGUUGUAACAUUUGAUGAAGUGAUGGCUACAGCAAGGAACUUAUCAAACUUGACUCUUGCUCAUGAGAUUGCUGUAAAUGAGAACUUUCAAUUGAAACAAGAGGCUCUCCCAGAAAAGAGUUUGGCUGGUCGAGUGAAGCACAUUGUUCACCAGGCCUUCUGGGACGUCUUGGAUUCAGAACUAAAUGCUGACCCUCCUGAGUUUGAACAUGCCAUCAAACUGUUUGAAGAAAUCAGAGAGAUUCUUCUCUCUUUUCUCACUCCCGGUGGCAACCGGCUUCGCAACCAAAUCUGUGAAGUUUUGGACACAGACCUCAUUAGGCAGCAGGCUGAGCACAGUGCUGUUGACAUCCAAGGCCUGGCCAACUAUGUCAUCAGUACGAUGGGAAAGCUGUGUGCUCCCGUGCGAGAUAAUGAUAUCAGAGAGUUAAAGGCUACUGGCAACAUCGUGGAGGUGCUGAGACAAAUAUUCCAUGUCCUGGACCUCAUGCAAAUGGACAUGGCCAAUUUUACAAUUAUGAGUCUCAGACCGCACCUUCAACGCCAGUUGGUGGAAUAUGAGAGAACCAAGUUCCAGGAAAUUUUGGAAGAAACUCCAAGUGCUCUUGAUCAGACUACAGAAUGGAUAAAAGAAUCUGUAAAUGAAGAAUUAUUUUCUCUUUCUGAGAGUGCUUUAACUCCUGGGGCCGAAAAUACCUCCAAGCCAAGCCUGAGCCCUACUUUGGUGCUAAAUAAUAGUUACUUGAAACUGUUACAGUGGGAUUAUCAGAAAAAAGAAUUACCAGAGACACUUAUGACAGAUGGAGCACGUCUUCAGGAACUAACAGAAAAGCUGAAUCAAUUGAAAAUUAUUGCCUGCCUGUCCCUAAUUACCAACAACAUGGUGGGUGCUAUUACAGGAGGCCUGCCUGAGCUUGCAAGCAGGUUAACAAGGAUUUCAGCUGUUCUACUUGAAGGCAUGAACAAAGAGACCUUUAACUUGAAGGAAGUCCUGAAUUCUAUUGGUAUUCAGACUUGUGUUGAGGUUAACAAGACCCUGAUGGAAAGAGGUUUACCCACUUUAAAUGCUGAGAUUCAAGCUAAUCUUAUAGGUCAAUUUUCAAGCAUUGAAGAGGAGGACAAUCCUAUCUGGUCCUUGAUUGAUAAACGAAUUAAGCUUUACAUGAGAAGGCUACUUUGUCUUCCAAGCCCUCAAAAAUGCAUGCCUCCUAUGCCAGGAGGCCUAGCUGUCAUUCAGCAGGAGCUAGAAGCCCUAGGCUCUCAAUAUGCAAACAUUGUGAAUCUCAACAAACAAGUGUAUGGACCAUUUUAUGCAAAUAUACUUCGAAAGCUGCUCUUCAAUGAGGAAGCCAUGGGGAAGGUAGAUGCUUCACCUCCUACUAACUAAAGAAGAACUGACAUUGGACGAGAGAUUGGAAAUCCAGUACUUUGGUAUCCAGUCCACUUCCAUUGAUGGCAUUAGAGAUCCAGCACAUUCUCAGUACUGUGGUGCAGUAUUAGCCCAAAUCUGUGUAAUGGGUAAUAUUAGCAUUACAGAAGACACACACAUCACAUAGACCCUCAGAAGACGUAAACAUCACAUAGACCCUAUUUGUGCAUCAUUUUCAAGUUUAAAACAAAUAUUUGUAAUGAACAGAAAACAAUUUGUAAUUAAUUAUAUUACCUAUAUAAUACUUGUAAAUGUUUUCUUAACCAUUUAUAUUUGGCUUAUGACAUUUAACCCCUAAGGAGUUGUUUUUCUCACUUGUUAUUAUCAAACCUAAUGGUUUUUAAUUUUGGUACAACUCCUUAAAGGGUUGAAGGUUGUGACAAUAACUGAGGGAACUGAUGUUCUGAAUAAAUGAUGUGAAGUAAACACAA